AUCGCACCAUUGCACUCCAGCCUGGACAGCAAGAGUGAAACUCCAUCUCAAAACAAACAAACCAAACAAAAAUGAACAUUUACUGCCAUACACACUUCCUGGGGGUCAGGGAUCCCAGAGUGUCUCCGCUGUGUCAGUAUGUCUCAGGGUUUCCUGAGGCUGCAGUCAUUAUGCCCGCUAGGGCUUGGGUGGGACUGAAGCACCUGCUUCCAAGUUGCCUCACUCACAUACCUGGCAAGUUGGUGCCGUUGCUGGCAGGAAGCCUGCUUUUCUUGCCAGGUGGACUUCUCUGAGGGGUGCGUGAAUGCCUUCACUACAGGGCAGCUGACUUCCCUCAGGACACAUGAUUCAGGAGACCAGGGGAAAGCUGCAGUGUCAUUUUAUCACAUAAUCCCAGAAGUAACACUCUGUCAUUUCUGCAAUAUCCUGUGGGUUACACGUCAGCAUUAUUCAUUGUGAGAGGUGACUACAUGAGGGUGAGUCCAGGAGGCAAGAAUUAUUGGGGGCUAUCAUGGAGGUUUGAUAACAUAAUUGGUAAGAAAUUCAGAUACACCUCAGACUUGAUUGUGGCAUACCAGUGUGUUGUAAAACUUGUGAGAAUGGCUUGCCUUAGAAAGACAAGUAGUCCAUCCAGUGUCUUAUUCUUAUGUUAAGUUGGGAUUGCUAUUUUGUUACCCUUGGGCCUCUAUAUACAAAGCCUCUCAUAGUAAUAGAUCUAAUUGGGUUGAAGUUUAGUAUUAUGUAUAUGCCCUCUGCUUUUAUUAGUAGAUUUUACUUUCGUGAAAGGAACAUAUAAACUUCAUUAUUGCAUUUUUGUAUAAAUGCAGCUGGGGACAUGGUUUUAUUACCCAAUGUCCAUUUUGUAAAUAUUUAGAGAACUUUUUUUUUGCAUCAUAAAUCAGUAUAAAUAGAAGCUUGGUUUCCAUUGUUGCCCUGGCUAUGAGGAAGCUGAGAGUGAAAUUUGUCGUUCAAGUGUGGCAGUUAUGUUACUGACUGGCGUAUUUAUAUUCUCCUUUAUUUGAUAUUUUGCUAUGAGAUGUUCCAGUUUACUUGUGGGAAAAAAAGCCAGGUGUUCUUGAACUCAACAAAUAUUUAUUGAAUUCCACUUGCUGGCCAGACAGCAUUCCAUGUGCCCCAGAUAUGGCACUGGACAGAUAGAUAAGGUCCCCACUCGCCUACAGCUUCCAACCUGGUCGUAAGAAAAUACCUUAGCUUUUGCUCCAUAAUGUGGAAGAAUUGGCCUCAGAGAAAACCUAAUUCAUAUGUACCACGUUUCUACCCAUUCAAGUUUUAUUUCAUAAUUUUUUUUUUUUUUUUUUUUUUUUUGAGAUGGAGUCUUGCUCUGUCACCCAGGCUGGAGUACAGUGGCACAAUCUCAGUUCAGUGCAACCUUUGCCUCCUGGGUUCAAGCGAUUCUCCUGCCUCAGCCUCCCGAGUAGGUGGGAUUACAGGUGCAUGCCACCAUGCCUGACUAAUCUUUUGUAUUUUUAGUAGAGAUGGGCUUUCACCAUAUUGGCCAGCCUGGUCUUGAACUCCUGACCUCAGGUGAUCCACCUGCCUCAGACUUCCAAAGAGCUGGGAUUACAGGCGUGAACCACGAUGCCUGGCCGUAUUUCAUAAUUCUAUCUUUCCAUAGAAAGAAUUGGCUGGGGCACGUAUAACUAAUGUGAGUUACUGAUUUCAGAGGAAGCUUUUGGAAGUGGUUGAUAGGCACUGAAUGGGAUGGGGUGGUGAGUGGUUUAAAAUAACACUUGAACCUUUGGAUUCAAAUGGUUUUAAAUGCAUCUCAGAAAAGUGAAAGGUGAAUGGGAGAGCUACAUCCAUUGAGAGCAAGGGUUCAUCAGCUAGGGCUGUGGCUUAAACUAAGCAGAUAUUCUUUCCUGGCAGUUCUACAGGCCAGAAGCCUAAGAUCAAGGCGUCAUGAGGGUUGGUUUCUCUGAGGCUCCCAGACAGUCAUCUUCUCCCUGUGUCUUCACGGGGUCUUUAUUCUGUGUCUGUGUCCAAACUUCCUUUUCCUUUUUUUUUUUUUUUUGAGACAGAGUCUUACUCUGUUUCCCAGGCUGGAGUGCAGUGGCACUAUCUCAGCUCACUGCAACCUCCAUCUCCCAAGCUCAAGUGACUCUCCUGCCUCAGCCUCCUGAGUAGCUGGGAUUACAGGUAUGUGCCACCACGCCCGGCUAAUUUUUGUAAUUUUAGUAGAGACGGGGUUUCACCAUGUUGGUCAGGCUGGUCUCGAACUCCUGACCUCGUGAUCUGCUCACCUCGUCCUCCCAAAGUGCUGGGAUUACCGGCAUAAGCCACCAUGCCCAGCCCAAACUUCCUUUUCUUAGAGGGUGGGCUUUAUCUGUGGUUCUUAGUUAGCCUCACCUUCAUUCUUCCUUUUGGUGUUACGGUCUUGCUUACUGCUUUGGGAAUGGAUUUGUUGAAACUACAUGUGACUAGUUUAGGGACCCAGUAGGAGGUUUUACUAUAAGUGUAAAUUAACAUGUGCCUUUGGGGGACCUUAAAAGUUUUUGUCAUUGGGCCAUGAGAUCUGAGUGCAGCUGGUAGAACCUCCUUGUUUUCUUUGGUAUGAGAACUCCUGGGCUUUUGUUGGUUCCUUCCGUUUUCUCCGGUGUAUUACCAUUUCACAUCACAGUGAUAUUAUCCAGAUAACACCCAUGAUUUGUUUUUAACGGAGUUUCACUCUGUUGCCCAGGCUGGAAUGCAGCGGUGCGAUCUUGGCUCACUGCAACCUUCACCUCCUGGUUCAAGCGAUUCUCCUGCCUCAGCCUCCCAAAUAGCUGGGACUGCAGGUGUGCACCACCACGCCUGGCUAAUUUUUGUAUUUUUAGUAGAGGCGGGGAUUCGCCAUGUUGGCCAGACUGGACUUGAAUUCCUGACCUCAAUUGAUCCACCCACCUUGGCCUCCCAAAGUGCUGGGAUUACAGGCACGAGCCAAUGCACCUGGCCACACCUGUGAUUUAUUUUAUUUCAUUUGAGAUUUCAGACUUUGUCGCUUGUUCUUUCUGUAGAAGUUUUUUCAUAGAAGUAUGUUGUUUCAAAAGCAACCUUCAAAUAGUAGACUUAGCUUGGAUGAGAAUCUAAAAGUCUUUGAGUCCAACAACCAAGCAGGUCCCCUGUCCAGGAAGUACCUUAUAGCUGAUGUUUGAGUAUCCCUGCAGAUGGGAACUCACUACCUCCUGAAGCACCUUACUUCUACCCUUGGAAUAGUAACAGAGAUUAAAAUGUCCUUCCUUAAUUUGAGGUGAAAUCUGCCUUCUUGUCCAUUUUACACACACUAACCUUCCUUCCACCAUGCAAGCUGAGAGAGAGCCAGGUUGAGCCUGUGUUUCCACAACAACUCUUCUCAGACCUCCUGCUGCCACCUACCAUGCACUUGCUCUUCACUGGCUAGGUUCCAGUUGCUCUGUACCUUUCCUAAAGUGUGGUGACCAGAAUUUGGCACAGUGAGGGAAGGUUCCAGAGCCCUUUAGUGUUAUCGGGGGCACAGAGCUUGGGCUUUGGAGUCGCUCAGAUCUUGAGUUGAUAUGCACUUCUUUGUCCUUGAGCAAAUGAUUGAACCUUCUUGGACUCUCAGUUCCUCAUUAAUAAAAUGAAGAUGAAACAAGAUGAGAUGGACUGUGCACAUUUCCUGAUGGGGGCUGGUAUGUGCUGGUGCCCAGUGCAAAGUGGCUGCUGGCAGAAUGGUGAGUCACCAGUACCUGCUCCCUUCACUGAGUGCUUCCUGUGUGCCUGGCACCAUUGCUCAGGGCUUUACAUGGACUUACUCAUUUCAUUUUCACUGCAGCCUAGAGCGUAAGUAAGUAUUUGCUUUAUCCCCAUCUUAUAGAUGAGGCAUUUGAUUCUCAAAAAGGUUUCAUAGCUUGCCCAUGUUCUAGCAGCUAGUAAAAGGAGAAGCCAGAGUUUUCAUUUAGGUGGGAGUCCUCAACCUGCUUUCUUAACUGCUGUGAUCUGCACUGUGGCAUGAGAGUUUGUCUUAAUGUAAAUGCACAUGUAAUAGCAUUAUUCACAUUGCCUGAGACUGUGGAAGCUCCUUUGGCAACCAGAUGCCACAGGGGACUCAUUUCAUGCUUUUAGAAGACUUGAGCCACUACAUGCCCUGGGAACUGUGUUGCUUCCCCACUGGCCAUCACUCUUGCUUUUGUAAGGGAUGUCACAUUGAGCCAUUAAGUGUCAUCUCUGGAACUCAUGACUCUGUUAUUCCACAUAUUAGGUUUUCUUUGUAGCUUUGUGUCAACUCCAAGCCAGGUAAAUAAAUCUUGGAAGAACCAAGUUACAGAUGUGAGUAAAAGAGGGGAUGGCAGGGGGCAGAAGUCAGGGCAGGCCCUGUGACUUGCCACCAGCAUCCUCCCUUCGGGGGAGGUCCUUUCAUCUGGGUGCUAGCUGGAGGAAUUGGCAACGUCGGAGAUAAAGGUGUAGAUGCACCAGCUGAACGUCUUGCUCUGUUUCCCAUUUUACGUAUAAGAUGGGUGAUGGCAUGCUGCAUUCAGAUCCCCAUGGGUGUAUUUGGGAUUUGGGGUGGGGGAUUGUGUGUAGAAGGCAGGAAAGAUUGCCCAGCAACUCUCAUUUGAAUUGAGGGUGGAAGCGGUUCUCGGGCACAGUAUGCCAAGGCCCAGGGCGUCCAAGGGACAGAGCAGAGAUCACAGAUGCUGAACGGGUGGGGAAGGAGCACUAGGCAGGGCAUUUCUGAUGAGACUUUGAUUUGGGAGGUACGAAAGUUGUAUGAGGAAUCUUGAUAAACUGCUUAGAGUGAAUGGAGAUGAGUAGGAAUCACCACCAUUCACAUACUGGCUCUGCAAGCCACUCAGCACAGCUCUGCACCUGCUCUUAUGGAGGAGAAGACAAGCAGAAGAGAAUGUUCUGAUCUAGAAGAGUUCGUGUAAGAGCAUGAAGGCAACAGCACUUGAGAUGUGGUGCACAUGAGCAAAAUUUCAGUUUAUGUGGAAUUUAAGAUUAACAGAUUAAAAGGUAAAAUUCUCUCCCUGGUACCAAAAAAAAAAAAAAAAUCCAUGUACUCCCUCUCUCUCUUUUUUUUUUGUUUUUUUUUUUGGAGAUGGAGUCUCGCUCUGUCCCCCAGGCUGGAGUGCAGUGGCAUGAUCUCGGCUCACUGCAAGCUCCGCCUCCCAAGUUCACGCCAUUCUCCUGCCUCAGCCUUCCGAGUAGCUGGGACUACAGGUGCCCGCCACCACACCUGGCUAAUUUUUUUUUGUAUUUUUAGUAGGGACGGAGUAUUCCCUCUCUUGACUGAUGUUUCAGCAGUAUGUGGACAGAUUCUUUUUUAAGGUAAAUGACCAGGGGCUUGUAAUAUGAGUGUCACUUAGGCAACAGGACAUUUCAAUGAAAUGGUGAUGGAAAUAGGUUCUUUUUGUAGAUUGUGAGCUCUUGGGAGCAUGGAUUUUGCUAAAUAUACUGAUUUUUAAAUUUUUUUGACAUCUAGCAUGGUGCAUUUCACAUAGGAGUUUUUCAAGAAGUACUCAUUUCACAGGCAUCUUGAAUGAUAGAUGUUUGGUAAGAACUGCGCAAGACAGUGUACUAAUCACUCAUUCUCAUUCAGCCUCUCAAGCUAUCAUGGUUGGUUAGUAAUAACAUUUCAAAAUUAUAUUUGUCCCUUAGGCUAGCAGAGAAUACUGUUUAACAGGUUUUUCUUGAAAAGUAGGAGUAGCGAGCUAGAGUUGUCUCUAGGUGGGGUAAAUAAAACAUCUCCCACCCCACCCAAAUUGAAGCUGAAUACCUUCAAUUCACUACUGUGCGCAUAUUCAUGUUUCAUGCUGAGCAGUUCACUUGAGACUUUCUCACGGAAAGAAGUGCGAUACAGUUGGUGGUAGUCUUAUAUUUGCUACGUGCUCAUGUGUUGUCUGAUGAUAGAAUGCAGUGGUCAAAUAUUGCACAAUUUACGCCAGAGGAGGAGAAUUCCCAUCAACUCUCCAACCAUCAUAAAUACUUUAUUCCACACAAUAAGGAAAUUGAACUUUUCAGAAGAAUGAUAUAGAACAUCUAAAAUAGGUUAAACUUGGAGGAAUUAUACUGUCCAUUGUAAAAUUGGAGCCACUCUUGAAAAAUUGCUGCAUGCCCCACUGAAUGCUAGAGCAAGACAUGCAGUCCCAGCUCCAGGGGCUUCCAGAGUGAUUGAGGCAGGGCUGUGGGCUGCUUUCCUGAAGCCUGACUCCUUUCUUUCCUCAUUACACUGCCACAGAUGGUGGCAGAUACAGCAUGGAUUGGCAUAAGUCACUCUCUACUACCUGCAGAAUAAAGGCCCAAUUUCCUAGUGCAGCUUGCAAAGUCCUUCUCAUCUGCCACCUUCCUGCCUUUGUGAUUUCUCCUCCUGGGACUCCUGCACCCCCUUUUUUUUUUUUAAUUUUUCUUUUCUUUUUUUUGAGAUAGGGUCUCCAUCUGUUGCCCAGGCUGGAGUGUGGUGGCGCGAUCAUAGCUUAUUGCAGGCUUGACCUCCUGGGCUCAUAUGAUCCUCUUGCCACAGCCUCCCAGAUAGCUGGGACCACAGGCACAUGCCACCCCGCCUGGCUAAUUUUUUGUAUUUUUUUAUAGAGACGGGAUUUCUCCAUGUUGCCCAGGCUGGUCUCGAGCUCCCGGGCUCAAGCGAUCUGCCCGCCUCAGCCUCCUACAGUGUUGGGAUUACAGACGUGAGCCACUGCACCCAGCCACUCCUGCACCCUUACCUUUUCGCCGCCCUGGCCGGCUGGACGACUGCACCCAUUUCACCCGGCAUUCUUGUGCCUGACUGUGCUCUGGCCAUUUCCUGUGUCUGGAAUACCCCCAUUCUCCCAUGCUCAGCCCCGUGGACUGUGUUUAUUCGUAAUCACACCUCAGAGCCCUUCCCCUUCUCCAUGGACUCCACCCCUGCUGUGUAGAUGGCCCCAACAUCAUUUUGCUGAGUGGAGUGCCACUGCAAGGCAUGGCAUGGAGGAGCCUGACUGCAUAGGUGGCGGCACCUUGAGGGCCUUACAGACCUGGCAGUUGAAGGGAGAGUCCCGUAUUCUCAGAGUAAAAGUUGUUUCUGGAAUUGAUCUCGCCAAAAAGGACAUCUUUGGAGCCAGUGAUCCGUAUGUGAAACUUUCAUUGUACGUAGCGGAUGAGAAUAGAGAACUUGCUUUGGUCCAGACAAAAACAAUUAAAAAGACACUGAACCCAAAAUGGAAUGAAGAAUUUUAUUUCAGGGUAAACCCAUCUAAUCACAGACUCCUAUUUGAAGUAUUUGACGAAAAUAGACUGACACGAGACGACUUCCUGGGCCAGGUGGACGUGCCCCUUAGUCACCUUCCGACAGAAGAUCCAACCAUGGAGCGACCCUAUACAUUUAAGGACUUUCUCCUCAGACCAAGAAGUCAUAAGUCUCGAGUUAAGGGAUUUUUGCGAUUGAAAAUGGCCUAUAUGCCAAAAAAUGGAGGUCAAGAUGAAGAAAACAGUGACCAGAGGGAUGACAUGGAGCAUGGAUGGGAAGUUGUUGACUCAAAUGACUCGGCUUCUCAGCACCAAGAGGAACUUCCUCCUCCUCCUCUGCCUCCCGGGUGGGAAGAAAAAGUGGACAAUUUAGGCCGAACUUACUAUGUCAACCACAACAACCGGACCACUCAGUGGCACAGACCAAGCCUGAUGGACGUGUCCUCGGAGUCGGACAAUAACAUCAGACAGAUCAACCAGGAGGCAGCACACCGGCGCUUCCGCUCCCGCAGGCACAUCAGCGAAGACUUGGAGCCCGAGCCCUCGGAGGGCGGGGAUGUCCCCGAGCCUUGGGAGACCAUUUCAGAGGAAGUGAAUAUCGCUGGAGACUCUCUCGGUCUGGCUCUGCCCCCACCACCGGCCUCCCCAGGAUCUCGGACCAGCCCUCAGGAGCUGUCAGAGGAACUAAGCAGAAGGCUUCAGAUCACUCCAGACUCCAAUGGGGAACAGUUCAGCUCUUUGAUUCAAAGAGAACCCUCCUCAAGGUUGAGGUCAUGCAGUGUCACCGACGCAGUUGCAGAACAGGGCCAUCUACCACCGCCCAGUGCCCCAGCUGGGAGAGCGCGUUCAUCAACUGUCACGGGUGGUGAGGAACCAACGCCAUCAGUGGCCUAUGUACAUACCACGCCGGGUCUGCCUUCAGGCUGGGAAGAAAGAAAAGAUGCUAAGGGGCGCACAUACUAUGUCAAUCAUAACAAUCGAACCACAACUUGGACUCGACCUAUCAUGCAGCUUGCAGAAGAUGGUGCGUCCGGAUCAGCCACAAACAGUAACAACCAUCUAAUCGAGCCUCAGAUCCGCCGGCCUCGUAGCCUCAGCUCGCCAACAGUAACUUUAUCUGCCCCGCUGGAGGGUGCCAAGGACUCACCCGUACGUCGGGCUGUGAAAGACACCCUUUCCAACCCACAGUCCCCACAGCCAUCACCUUACAACUCCCCCAAACCACAACACAAAGUCACACAGAGCUUCUUGCCACCCGGCUGGGAAAUGAGGAUAGCGCCAAACGGCCGGCCCUUCUUCAUUGAUCAUAACACAAAGACUACAACCUGGGAAGAUCCACGUUUGAAAUUUCCAGUACAUAUGCGGUCAAAGACAUCUUUAAACCCCAAUGACCUUGGCCCCCUUCCUCCUGGCUGGGAAGAAAGAAUUCACUUGGAUGGCCGAACGUUUUAUAUUGAUCAUAAUAGCAAAAUUACUCAGUGGGAAGACCCAAGACUGCAGAACCCAGCUAUUACUGGUCCGGCUGUCCCUUACUCCAGAGAAUUUAAGCAGAAAUAUGACUACUUCAGGAAGAAAUUAAAGAAACCUGCUGAUAUCCCCAAUAGGUUUGAAAUGAAACUUCACAGAAAUAACAUAUUUGAAGAGUCCUAUCGGAGAAUUAUGUCCGUGAAAAGACCAGAUGUCCUAAAAGCUAGACUGUGGAUUGAGUUUGAAUCAGAGAAAGGUCUUGACUAUGGGGGUGUGGCCAGAGAAUGGUUCUUCUUACUGUCCAAAGAGAUGUUCAACCCCUACUACGGCCUCUUUGAGUACUCUGCCACGGACAACUACACCCUUCAGAUCAACCCUAAUUCAGGCCUCUGUAAUGAGGAUCAUUUGUCCUACUUCACUUUUAUUGGAAGAGUUGCUGGUCUGGCCGUAUUUCAUGGGAAGCUCUUAGAUGGUUUCUUCAUUAGACCAUUUUACAAGAUGAUGUUGGGAAAGCAGAUAACCCUGAAUGACAUGGAAUCUGUGGAUAGUGAAUAUUACAACUCUUUGAAAUGGAUCCUGGAGAAUGACCCUACUGAGCUGGACCUCAUGUUCUGCAUAGACGAAGAAAACUUUGGACAGACAUAUCAAGUGGAUUUGAAGCCCAAUGGGUCAGAAAUAAUGGUCACAAAUGAAAACAAAAGGGAAUAUAUCGACUUAGUCAUCCAGUGGAGAUUUGUGAACAGGGUCCAGAAGCAGAUGAACGCCUUCUUGGAGGGAUUCACAGAACUACUUCCUAUUGAUUUGAUUAAAAUUUUUGAUGAAAAUGAGCUGGAGUUGCUCAUGUGCGGCCUCGGUGAUGUGGAUGUGAAUGACUGGAGACAGCAUUCUAUUUACAAGAACGGCUACUGCCCAAACCACCCCGUCAUUCAGUGGUUCUGGAAGGCUGUGCUACUCAUGGACGCCGAAAAGCGUAUCCGGUUACUGCAGUUUGUCACAGGGACAUCGCGAGUACCUAUGAAUGGAUUUGCCGAACUUUAUGGUUCCAAUGGUCCUCAGCUGUUUACAAUAGAGCAAUGGGGCAGUCCUGAGAAACUGCCCAGAGCUCACACAUGCUUUAAUCGCCUUGACUUACCUCCAUAUGAAACCUUUGAAGAUUUACGAGAGAAACUUCUCAUGGCCGUGGAAAAUGCUCAAGGAUUUGAAGGGGUGGAUUAAGCACCCUGUGCCUCGGGGGUGGUUGUUCUUCAAGCAAGUUCUGCUUGCACUUUUGCAUUUGCCUAACAGACUUUUGCAGAGGCGAUGGCAGAGAGCAGCUGCAGGCAUGGUCCCUGGAGCCGAGCCUUCACCACGCACUCGUCCAAGUUCGGAUGCGGGAACCUGGUCCCAGCUUGAGUUCCUGCCUUUCCCACCACAAAUUAUCAACUGGUUGAUGUGUACACUAAUUACAUUUCAGGAGGACUUAAUGCUAUUUAUGUUGUGCCUCUGCAGGCAAAGCCCUUAAUAAAUAUUUUACAUCCUUUCUAAUGACAAUGAAUGGAAUUAAUCACUCAACAGGUAUAGUAUUACGACUCAUGUUUACUUUUUAAAAUGAUUUAGACCGAUUUUCAGAUUUUAUUUCGUUAUGAUUAAAGAUGUCUCAUGUACUUGGAAAAGUGAGCAUUUUUUUUUUUUUUGUAUUUCACUUUCAUACCAGGCUUAAUGUCAAUGACAUUUUUAUUUUUGAAGUACUCUGACACCUCCACCCUCUACUUUAUUAGAAUUGGAAGGCAAAUUUUUGUCCAAAAACCUACAGACAAGUACUUUGAGAGAAUUUCCAAUAUAAUAUUAGACAUAAUGAUAAUUUUUUCCAUACUCAGAAUGAAAAACUGGAUAUUACGUUUUUGUUUUGGGGUUUUUUUGUACAAAUUUAGCUAAUAGCUACAGGCUGAGAGAAUUGUAACAUAGCAUGACAAAUUUUGUGUUGACUUGAAAGGAAUCACACCAUUAUUCCUUAGAAGUAAUUACAUGUGUUCUAACACAUUUGAGACAGGGUUGGACUCCCAUUUCUCAUCCGAGAAAUUACUUAACCCUUCCUGGCGCUGUACAGUCAUCUUUUAUUCUAUUUCCUCUUUGCUGUUUGUAGUAGAGACAUUUUGAAUGAAACUUGGCACUGCUUGAUUCAAAACUGUGGAAACCAGAUCUGUUUAGUCUCCUGUUUGUAUGCGUUUGCUAAUGGUAGCUAAAUAACCAGUUUUUGUUGUAAAUGCACCAAUUCUGAAGGCACUUUAUGUACUACAUGGAGGUCAUAUCUGGUUUUGUUUUUAUUUUUUUAUCAUGAACAUUAAAUGUGAUGAUGAUUUCUUUUCCCUGCACACAUCUUUCCGGUGCAAUAUCUAUCAAUUGUGAAUCUGGCUGCUGGUGUAUAAAAACCUGGAUGUAAAGCUGAGCCUACAGACCUGUCCUCACCAACUGUUUUGUGAUUUCUACUCAACUACAAAGAUUUAUUUAAUGUACUCUUAAUCUAACUGAGUUUUGUUACCAAUGACCUGUUGCAUGCUUCAAUACCGUGUACUGCCUGAGUUGUGCCUCUUGUGUGCUAGAUUAAAAGUGAGACAGAGACUUGACUUGAUCCUCUGAGCUCAAGCUAUUGAGCUGGUAGUGGCAGAGGACUGAGGGUACCUGCACAGUUUGAUUCUUUUCCACGUGUAAGUCUCCAUUGCAGAAUUGUCGUGCUUUGAGAAAACACCUGAGGCAGUGUGGGAGUUGAACGACCCUGCUGUCCUUUUUAACCUGUGUUGUCCUAGACCCUGUCGGGGCAGUCAGGGGACACUAGAGAUUUGAUCUCAUGCGAGUCAUCAAUAGGACAAAAAAGUUGUGGUUUGGGGAGGUCUGUUUGUUACAUAAAAAGGACCUUUCGGUGUAAGAAAUUGCCGUUUUUACCCUGCCCUGGCUGGCAUGUGAGAAGCCAUGGAAGGUUGUGGUUGUAAAUGAGUUGUCUAAAGGGGUGCAGAGGCCUGAGGUUUCUAAAAGAAGGUAGAUUUCUACAGAGCUGAGUGUUGGUUCCUUUUUCUUAUUGGUUGAAAAUUACCUGGUAGUGAUCAGAAAACUUAGAUGCUAUGUAACUAAAAAAAAAAAAAAAAAAAAAAAAAAAAAAAAAAAAAUUCCCGCUCAUGAGUUUUGACUAUUGGUGAGAUGUUUUCCGCUACAGUUAACAUGACAAAUGUCUCAGUGGCAAAAAUCCCCUUUUUGUAAGCCCCCAUAGUCUAGAGGCAGUUUUCUUUUUAAGAAUCAUGCCAGAGCCUGAGUCGAGCAGUAUGCUUUCUUGGUUUUUGAGAGUAAUUGUGUAAUUGUAGAGGGAGAAAUCCAAUUCUAACCUAAGAACUGGGAUUCUUCUGUCAUCUUGUAAACCGUAUAUUGAAAAAAACAGAAUGUCACUAAAUGCAUAUUAAGUCAAGUAUUGGAAAGUAUAAAAGAAAAAUCAUUCUGACAAUUUCUAAGCCAGAAGCAAACAAGAAUUACUGAAAUCUACCCCAUGAAUACUUGGAAGGCAGUAAUUGUGAGUGACACCUCAGUUCAUCAACCCCUUAAUAAUAUCAGCUUAAUUUUAAUGACAACUAAAUAUGCUGAAGUGAGGAUUUAGUAUUUUUUAAAAAAGCAAAACAAGGUUCAGUAGUCCUCAGCAAUUCUCCAAGUUUCUCUCUUUGCCUAAAAUGGUCAUAGAUCUUGAUUUCUCUGAAUCGUGAUGACCACACCCAGUCAUCUUCACAGCAUAAUUGCAGGUGGCAGUAAAGAGAGUGUGCUGGGUAAGGAGCAGUUGCUGGGUCAUUCCUUGGGCCCCGACCUGCCCGGGGAGUAGCCCUGGGGGAGAGAGGGCAGUGUUGCCUAUCCCAGAGGUCCCAGCAGUCACACUGCUCUGCAGGCCGGGCUCUCUUUAUAGCCAGAGAAAUCACCUUAAUGCAGUCUCUUUAGUUGUCUGCUGAAGCUGUAGUUAUUAUGGGCCACUUACAUGAGGCUGAGAAGUACGUGCCGGAGCUCACACACUGCCUGUUGCGGUUCUCUUAACAUCAGUUAUCACAGCUGCCUGUGGGUCCCGGGUAUUUCCAUUCCUGCCCCUUGUUGGCCCGAGGAAGGAUGUGGAAAGAGCACCUGGUGGGAUGAAGGUCCAACAGCCUGUGCCUCUCCACUGCUGGCCCUGGAGCCGGCAGCAGUGAGGCAUUCAUUGUCUGUGUUGCGGUGUAUUCCCAGCUUCAGUGCUCUUUUCCUUUUUGCCUGAAAUGUUUAUGCUUCUCUGCAGCCAGUCCUCUAACAAAUCUCAAGAACAAAGGUAAGACACUUGGUUUUUGUUUCCAGGACCCUUCAGAAGGUGACAUCAGAUAUUCCCUAAAUUCAGACAAUGAGGGAUACAGAGCGACUUGGCAUGUAUUAUUUCUCCCAUGUAAGGACAAAGGGACAGAUUAUUAUUGUUAUUUCUGAGACAGAGUCUUGCUCUGUAGCUCAGGCUGGAGUGCAGUGGCUCAAUCUCAGCUCACCACAACCUCUGCCUCCUGGCUUCAAGCGAUUCUUCUGCCUCAGCCUCCCCGAAUAGUUGGGAUUACAGGCACCCACCACCACGCCUGGCUAAUUUUUGUAUUUUUAGUAGAGAUGGUUUCACCAUGCUGGCCAGGCUGGUCUUGAACUCCUGACCUCAGGUGAUCCUCCCGCCUCAGCCUUCCAAAGUGCUGGGAUUACAAGCAUGAGCCACCGCACCCGGCCUCACAGUGACAGAUUCUGAGAAACAGCAUGCAAAACAUUUGAACCAUUUUCUACAUCUCCCAUUGUUGCAUAGAGAGUGUGCACCGCUGCUAUCUUGCCAGAUCCACACUGGUCCUCCCGAAAGCCAGGUUCAUACACAGCAACUUUUUAAUUAUUCUAACAGUUACCCAUUAACAGUCGACUCCUGUAUUUCUGAGAGUCUUGUACUCACCUCUGAAAUUUAAAAACGUAUAAAGAGAGCCUGGGUUAAUCAGUUCUGCAGCCCCUACGUGACACUGUGCUAGUUCUCCUUCUUCUGUCUCCUCCUUACCCUGGCCCUGCACCCCUGUACUUAAGAGGGAGAGGUGGGAGGUGCUGUCUGGUAUCAUUUGCUGCCUCGCCAGUAGAGGGUGCCGCUGUGCAGGGUAACUGCCCGCCUGCUCCCUUCCUGACCUCCCCUGACCCCGAAGAUCACUACCUCUGUCAUUCAGGCAUUGGGGUACAUCCUGAUAAGUCGUGUCAGAACUGCCAAUUUCAGGACUGAGAUGUGUUUUUAAAAAACAAAUCCUUAUAAACUCCACUUUGUACUUUAGAUUUUAAAACUGGGGAAAAAUGUGAUAUUCUUUGGACCACUUUUUUAAUUUAUAUAAGCCUUAAUGAACAGUGUCUAUACAUUUGCAUACACACACCCCCACCCCAGAGUGUUCUCAGUAUGUCAGAGAAAGUGCCACAGCAUUAGGACGGGAGCUUGGAGAACGUUUUCUAGAAAAGGGUUAGCUUCCUGUUGGCAUGAAAUUUUCCAAGCAAACCUCAUUAAACAUCUGUUGUUUGUUAAAGAUGUUCCACUGAAAGCAACGCAUGUUUCAAAGGCACGUCUUUCCGUUCGUUGGUUUUCUGUGUGUAAGGAGUAGCAUUGCUGUUGGCGCCUAACCUCGCGUGCACUGCAUUCUCAACCCCGUACCAGUGCAUCAUCAGAAGCCUUCCUCGUGACCAUAACUCUGUGUCUGCAGAUAUGUGUUCCCGUGUAAGCCAGUUUUCCCCUUUUACUCAGACUGAUUUCACCUAGAUUGUCACGGUUUCCUUCAUGUUAACUUUGCGUGACUUUGUUCUUCCUUUACUACUCUGUAUGUAAUAUAUAUACAUAUAUACGUACAUAUGCUGUCCAAAUAUAUUUGUAUAUAUUUGUAUAGCAUUUUUACACCUUUAUUGAGUAAUCUGGUUUCGAAAGGAGGUGAGAGUUUAGUCCCUUCUGCAGUUUUCUCCAAGCUGUGUCCUGUGAAUUUCAACCCUUGGAGCCUAAGAAAACCCUAGGAAGAUGAUGUUAAUUUGCUGUCAUUUCCUAAUUCAGGAUCUAUCAUCAAAUGAAACAUGAAAAAAACAGUGACUUUUAAGGUGAAAAGAGUUUCAAGCAUUCCAAAUAAAUUAUCAAUGUUUCAUAACUUUUUAUUAUAAACCCACCUCCUAAUAGGAAGCCAAGUACUAUUUGAUACAGUGGUAAAAACCAAACUACCUUGAAUUUUUUUAAGGCAACUUAUGAAUAAUGCUCAUUUUCACAGUCAGAAUAGCUUUAAAAUAUGGUUGAAUUUGAUACACACAGGAAGUUUUCUUGAAGAACAAUCCUUUCGCUUUUCUUUUUUCUUGAGAGAUCUAAAGAGAAACUGUAGAUUGUUUUCCUGACAGCAAAAGACUAAUGUGACAAAAUGAAGUCAUUGUAAAGAAGCGAUGCAACUUGUCAAAUAUUUAAUAAAGAAUUAUGGAAGCUGGAACAUUUUCUAC